GCUUUAAAAUGGCGGCAUUCAGUAUGCACCCCUGCUAAAGGCUCUCCCGGCACCGGGGCCACCUCGCGCAGCGCUGCUUUUGCUUCUGCCGCUAACAGAUGGCAUGUGCCGCUGUCGCUGCCGCUGCCCCUGCUGCUGCCGCUGAGAGCAGGGCCCCUUAGCCUCUGGGUUUGCGCUAGCAGCGUAAGGUUAUUUUUAAAAUACUUUUCCUAGAAGUCAUUUGCCUGCAACUUCAACGCUCUAGAACAUGGUCCUGCAUGUAACUUGAUGCAGAAGGGCCUGCAUAGAAGUAAGAGCAGUCAUAGAACUUCUGCAAGAAAGCUCUGCAUCUUGUUCCACAGGCCCCUCAUUCAGUGGGUUCUGAAAAGUGCCUUUUCUGAAAACUCUGCUGCUUGGAUUCUACUCUAGAGCUGUCUCUUUAUAAACCCCUCUCCCUACCAUACCGUUCCCUGCCCUCUCCACCUCCCCGCCGAACCUGGUGUGCUUGUAGUUUACUGUCAGCAGCUGGUCCAUUUCUUUUUUCUGUGAUUCUCAAUUUUCUUAGUCAUUUUCCCUCCACUUGAUUUUGCAACGAAACUUUUUUUGGGUUCUAACAUCCUUCCCAAUCUUGUUAUUUAAAGCUAAUAAAUAGGGAGAAAAACUUUUCUCCCCCUGAUCUGAGACCAUUCCACAAAUCGAAGGGCAGCCAGCAGCAUAUGUUUUUUGCAAGAAUAAUUGAAAACAUCAACUGCAGAGCCCAGAAUUCUUUUGAAAGUCUGCCGGUUAUUUAACAUAAAUUCGGCAAAGGAACAAAAUAAAGCAUUCAUUAUCUUAACAGUUGGCUUCUUAAGAGUUGGUCUCUAAUUUCAUUUUUAGUUAUUCUGAUAGUUUUUAUGAUUGGCUUUUUGUUUGACUAGACCAGAUUUGACUUUAAUGAAAACCUAAGUGUUAACAAAUAGACAUUUCACCAAAGCAACCUGUUAUCUCUUCGCACUUAGUUUGAAUUCAUUUUUAAUCCUUUAAUAGUCCACAGUAAUAUUGUCCUAAAGAGGGUACAUUGGAUUUUAAUUUUGCUUUCAAUAUGACGGCUGUCAAUGUUGCCCUGAUUCGUGAUACCAAGUGGCUGACUUUAGAAGUCUGUAGAGAAUUUCAGAGAGGAACUUGCUCUCGAGCUGAUGCAGAUUGCAAGUUUGCCCAUCCACCAAGAGUUUGCCAUGUGGAAAAUGGUCGUGUGGUGGCCUGUUUUGAUUCUCUAAAGGGUCGGUGUACCCGAGAGAACUGCAAGUACCUUCACCCUCCUCCACACUUAAAAACGCAGCUGGAGAUUAAUGGGCGGAACAAUCUGAUUCAACAGAAGACUGCCGCAGCCAUGUUCGCCCAGCAGAUGCAGCUUAUGCUCCAAAACGCUCAAAUGUCAUCACUUGGUUCUUUUCCUAUGACUCCAUCAAUUCCAGCUAAUCCUCCCAUGGCUUUCAAUCCUUACAUACCACAUCCUGGGAUGGGCCUCGUUCCUGCAGAACUUGUACCAAAUACACCUGUUCUGAUUCCUGGAAACCCACCUCUUGCAAUGCCAGGAGCUGUUGGCCCAAAACUGAUGCGUUCAGAUAAACUGGAGGUUUGCCGAGAAUUUCAGCGUGGAAAUUGUACCCGUGGGGAGAAUGAUUGCCGCUAUGCUCACCCUACUGAUGCUUCCAUGAUUGAAGCGAGUGAUAAUACUGUGACAAUCUGCAUGGAUUACAUCAAAGGUCGAUGCUCGCGGGAGAAAUGCAAGUACUUUCAUCCUCCUGCACACUUGCAAGCCAGACUCAAGGCAGCUCAUCAUCAGAUGAACCAUUCAGCUGCCUCUGCCAUGGCCCUGCAGCCUGGUACACUGCAACUGAUACCAAAGAGAUCAGCACUGGAAAAGCCCAAUGGUGCCACCCCGGUCUUUAAUCCCACUGUUUUCCACUGCCAACAGGCUCUGACUAACCUGCAGCUCCCACAGCCGGCAUUUAUCCCUGCAGGGCCAAUACUGUGCAUGGCACCCGCUUCAAAUAUUGUGCCCAUGAUGCACGGUGCUACACCUACCACUGUGUCUGCAGCAACAACACCUGCCACCAGCGUUCCGUUCGCUGCACCAACUACAGGCAAUCAGCUGAAAUUCUGAACAGCAGAGUUAUGGAGUAUCAGAAUCUUUCCAUGGAAACCUCCAUAUGGCCUUUCUAUAUAUAUUCUCGUAUGUCUUAUUCUACCAACACAACAAUAAGCGUGUUGCAGUCAAUGUAUUAAGCAAAGCAAACCUGCCAGCCAGCAAAUUCAAAUAAAAAAUAAAGCAUUAAAAAUCAAUGGAGAUGUUAAAACAACACAAAUAGAAAACUAGUAACUACCAUCCAUCCUAUUUGAAUUAUCAAGCAGAACAUGACCAUAAAAUUUGGUAACUUGUUACAUUACUCUUUGUGAUUUUCUAAUAACCAUGCUAAGUGUAUUUCCACAGUGAGCUUUUGGCUUACUAUAUACAUUCUUGGUGGAUAAAUUGUUCAUCUGUUUUUGAAGUGUUACCUUACUAUUUUGUUUACAAGAUAGUCUAUUGGGUUGAUUCAGGAUGUAACAAAUAUAUUCAGUACCAUUUCUUGUGUUGUAUUGUGUUGUGCUGUGUUAGGUUUUUACAUACUGUAGUGUUUUGCUGUAUAUGUGUGGUGUUUGAUUUCAACUAAAGUGUUAUUAGUGGGGAACAGAAGUAUAUGUGCUUAAGAACAUGACAGGUUCAUGCAAAUAUGCUCUCUUUCUUUAGAAUAUUUCUGUAGGUUUCUUGGGACUGACAUUUAAAACGCCUCACUUUUGAAUGUGCACAAAACCUGCUCAUUAACAUGCAUGUGUAUAAUUUGUACCUGCAGAUCUGAUGUUGCAUAAUACAAUCAAAUUACUAGAUUUUUUAAAGAGAGAAAUAAUUACCUGCACAAAGCAGAGAACUUCAUAAAACAUUAACCCCUAAUUCACUCUUCUUAAAUAGCUUGGCAAAUAAGACUUUACCUUUAAAUGAAUUUCUCAGCAUUUAUACUAAAAAUUAUGUAAAGUGCUCAUUAGAUUUUUUGUGUGUGUGGCUUGAGAAUCCCAUCUCCUAAAUUGAGUGUCUAAAACUGAGCCAUUUGUCAUCUUCAGCUGAGAAACUGGUACUUGGGAGCUUAAAAAUAUGCUAAUUACAAGUUAUAAAUCAAACGGAGAGAUGGGGGCAUGGAGAUAGUUUUUACGUACUGGAGGAAAGUGUGUAAAACCAUGGCAAUGUCACCUUUUACACAAAUGCCAUUUUCCAAAUGCAAAUGGCUCAUGCUCUUUAGACUACUCUUUGAAUAACAAGUAAGAUGCAAUCUAGCAAAAGUCAGUCAGGGUGAAAGAGAAUUGGUUGCAAAUGAGGACUUCCCUCCCCAAAUGGACAGUCUUCUCUGUUGAUCACAGAGGGAGCCUGAGUACAGGCUUGGAGAAAUGGCUAGGACAGGGAACAGGGAAGCACUUACAAUUAUUCCUUGAUUUAUUCAAAAGAACUGGGAAAGAUGGUUGUAGUUGUCUUUAGCUUCGGUUCAACUGAGUUUCGUUUUGUUAAACAGUUCAGUGAAGGAGAAAGCACCUGUGAUAUAUGGCAAGUGUCCCCCUGCCCAAACUUUAACAUCAGACCCUCUCACAUCAUAACCAAGCCUCUUUUAUGCUUGUUUGGAUUCGUUUGCCUUUAUAUAUGUUUGAAAAUGACAAUAGAAAGGGUUUUAUCACCCUUUGAAUGAGACAGAGUGGCUAUACUCCACAGAGCUCAGCUGAGUUCACAUUACUAAUAUUUAUGAAAGAAUUUUACAACCAAAUAAUUCCUGUGGUGUGUGACAUAUCUCAUCCACUCUACUCAUUUAUUAAUGUUAUUAUACAGUGGUGGAAACACAUGACAUUUUACAUCAAGUAAUAGAUUUAAUAUUUUCUAGUAAAUAGGCGCUCUUCCACCAGAAAGUAUAAAACCAUCAUAUACAUAUAUAUAUAUAUAUAUAAUGGUUUUUCUCCUUCAUGAAAAUGACAAGUAAAAAGCAAAUCUGAUUGAGGAUACCUUAAGCUGGCUAGAAGUGUUUGAAUCACAGAACAAUGGAAUUAGCAAAAUCCUUUUUAUAGUUGAUGGAACUGAAUCCAGGGGCAUAUGACUUGCCCAAGGCUACCUUAGCCAUUGUGGGACCCAGAAAUAUCUCCUGCUUCCCAUUGUUCCUCCUUUUCACAUUGUUUUUGCUUCAGAACAUUUGAUGCUCUCUUCCAAAGCAGACCCAUUUGGCUCAGAAUAUAAGAGAGCAAAAUUAGCUUUCUGGGAAUUGAUACUCUGUUGAUCUUAAUUAUCCAUCCAAAUCCUGAUCAACAGUGCUUUCUAAACAGCCUUGCUUGUAUUGAGUCAUUGUCAGCUGUUGACAAUGUUGCGUGGAAUUAGAGAUCAAGAGUUGUCCUGACCUUUACCUAUGGACUCUUUGAACCAGUUAAUUUCUAUUUCUGAAAUCUUAACAUUGCUAUAGAAGAAAGUAGUGUAUGCCUUUUUGAAAUUCAUCAUGUAUGGAACUGAGUUUUGUAUGAUCCGUGCCAGUGCCUCUCCAGAAGGGCAGAUCUGAUUACAUGAAUCCAGGAGGGAUGCACCUGAGCUAGUCUGGAUAUAUUCCUUAAAGGAGACAAGAACUUUUUUGUGCAAAAUGAACUUUUGUGUAGUUUGACAUCUGCAUGCAGUGAACUGUCUCACUUAACUUUUUCAACUUUGGGCAAAGAUAUACAUAAACCAUAGAUAAUAGACCUACAGUACAGCUGUUUUCAUGUUGCGUUAAGCACUGGAAGACAUUAACAAUGACUUACCUUAAAGUAAAAGGUUCCGUGAGGGGUAUUUAGGGCCACUGUAUUUUUGGUGCCACAAUUUUCUACAUUGUUGGCAUUUUAAAAGUUGUUUUCUAAAUGAACUUAAAGAAAGAAAGCUCAAAGCCCUAAAGUUUUGAUCAAAUUCAAUAGAGUUUUCAGAAAAAAAUACAAUUUUAAGAUAGCACUCUUUAAACUAGAUGUGCAAUGACUUAUUCAAAUUAUCUUUAUUCAAGAAAAGAGAAAAGAAGAAAGAUAAGUCAUUAGACUAUAAAUUUCCAUUUAAAAAGACAAGUCACAAAACUAAUCAGUGACUCUAAACAAAAAUUUACUGGAUGAAUUGUAUAUAUAAAAUUCUAAUCACUUAUGAUUCUUAGUUAACAUUUUAUAAGCUUUGUAUUUUACAGGGGCCUCUAUUUAUCCAAAUUUAUUGUUUUUGUCCAUUUUUCUCAGCCUUUUGCAAAAAAUAUGCAAGAGUGCUGAAACUUGGAUAAAACGGGUCAUGUAUACAGAGAAAAUAAUCUAAAAGUUAUCUUUAAGAGGGUUUUAGUAGUGUCAACUUUUUAAAAAAGUACUAUGUGACCAUAACAUACGUAUAUUUUAAAGAGGGAUUAAGAUUAAAUUAAAAUAAAUGGAUUCAUAAAAUUGCUAUUUAAAUACAGUAUUUACUUUUGUAAUUGAAGCAUGAUUCCACAACCAGCUGUGGCAUUUUAUUUCACUUUUCUAGAUCAGAGGCUUUAAUUUGUAGUUAAUCAUGAUGUGGAAAGUCAUCUUCUCUCUACUCCAUCAAUUUUUUUCAUCCGUUUUUGAACAUGCUGAAGCACUUUGAUCUUGCCAUAAGUGUUGUCCUAUACCACUAGGUGGUGUUCACUAAUGGGAGGGCCUCAGCUCACCGGCUCUCCAAUUUGGGAAAAAGCAAGUACCUCCUCCCUACCAUCAGCAGAAACUGAAUGAAAUUAAUCUUUGCAACUUGAAUCUGUUUUAAGUAGCAUUACCAAUAAGCAUAGUGGUAUCUGAAUAAGGAAUGACAUUUACAUUACAUUUUAUUAAAUAAGAGAGAAAGUUAAUGUGCUACUUGAAAUGUUAUUUGGUUCUUUGUCCCCCUCAUUGCAGAGUAUAGAUAAGGAUGCUCUUAGGUAAAAUGCAGCCACAAGUUUUCCGAGUUCCUUUAGUCUGUAGGGUAGGCUAUGAGGUACAGAAUGAUUAGAAACUGAAAUCCUCAUUAUUUUUCUCUCAAAUACAUUUCACAUACAUUGAAACAGAAAUAGGCAAAAUUUAUGAGGGAAAUCUGAUUUCCCAAUUCUGAUGAAUAGAUAUACUAAGACAGUAGCCUUGUUUAACCAGUGCCUGUAGAAGGCACUAGAAUAAAUAGCAUGUCCAAGAGUAUAACAACUUUUUUUGUAAAUUUAGUUACUAGCCUAAUCAAACUGUAAAUAUAACUCACUAAUUGGUACCAUAUUUUCAUUUUUCUUAUUGUUCAUCUUUAAGGUUUCAUUUUAUUGCUUUUUUGUAGCUCUAAGUAACUAAUCAAUUUAAUUUCAAAGGAAAGUUAAAGAAAGUUUAAGCUUUUACUGCAUGGAUUCUGCCCGCCUAGCUAGGUUCUGAACUGACACUGAAGUAUGACAAGAUACAGAUUAUAGUCCAAAACUAUCCUUUACAGUUCACAAUUUAAGAACAAAUUUAACUUUAUAUACAAAUAAUAAUUGUUAUCUAAUUAUAUUUAGUUGUUGCUUUGGCAACAAAAUUACAACAUGGCUACCUUUAGACAUUUGUGUAUGUGAACAUUUUACUUGUAAACUAUAGGUGAUUUGUGACAGUAUGAGCCUGUAGAAAAUACAGCUCAAAACUAUGAAAACAGACAUGGUUGAGUUCUUUUUUAAUCCCAAAGGCCCAUAUAUAAAAGCUGAAUUUGUGUCCUUGUGUGACUUUUUGUGAAAAAGUUUAUAACACAUGGAUUCUAGAAUCAGGCUUUAUAGUUUAUAGAAUUUGUUGUGUGGAUAGGGUUAUUCCACAGUAUUUAGACUUCAAAACGCAAUCAUUGCAUUUUUAAUACAUUACCUAACUUUUUUUAUAACUUAAUUCAAAAUUACCCCAUUCAAGUGGCAUAGCUGUAGCUGCAAAAAUUCUGUUUUCUGGAAUUACAUGAGCAAAUAUAGCUAUAUGAGGAUUAAUGUAUGACUAAAGCCUCUUUUGAAAUUAAUUCAUAUUUUUAAAACUAUACAUAAAGAUACUGUGGAAUGACCCCUUAACAGUGUUUAAGAAACAUAUGCUGCAGUUAAUUGACUGUCUCAGUUAGGGUGCGGAUGUGUGAGACACACCUUUUUUGCACUUAUGUACAUAGUCCAUGAAAGCAAUCCUUGGAGCUUUUUUUAAAUGUAAGAAGUCUGUGAUAAUAGUGGAAAAGUUAGUAAGAGAGAGUUAUUUCUAAGGCUUUGAAAAGGAGGGUGUUUUUGCUCUAAGACUUAACUAAAGCAUAAUGUUGCUUUGCUGUUACGGAGGCUUUCUAGUUUGCUACAGGUCACCAAAAGAGAAGGCUAGUAACAGGUAACAGGUCAGCCUCAGCUAACAGCACUGAACAAGAGUAGAAUAACUUCAUCUUUUAACAAGAUCAUUAGCAAAGAUUGUUUGCUUUUUAAAUUAAUCCCCCCUAUAAACACACACACACGUGUGCACACACACACACACACACACACACCGGGCAGUUUCUAGAACAAGUUUUCCUUUUUCAGUGGUUGUAAGCAGUGAAAUACCUCAUGUAUUACAAGAUAGAUAUUACCGUUAUGAUAGAAUAAGAUUUCAUCUUUCACAGAAAGUGAUCAGCUGAUAUAUGUGUCAGUUAAAAUGUUUAUCAAUUAAUAGGUAUUUAAGUGACAAAUUGUUAAUGUUGACCAUUGUUCCUCCUUUAAGAUCCAGUAACCAAAACCAAAUCGGUAACCAUUGAAAGAUGAUAUUUAACAGUUAAGGAUGGCCAGCAUAGGGCCGUUCAUUCCCUUCAACAAAGGGAAAAAAAAUGCUCCUGGCACAACUUUAUAACUGGCUUCAUUUACAUUAUACCUGUUCAGUGGAAGCUGUUUUUUGACCUACCUUUACCAGAUUACAAAGUAGUUAACUGUGCCACUUCAGCCUCCCACUGUUUUGUUUUAACUAAACAGAAGAGAACCAGCCAAAAUCUUACGUAACACAGGAGCUGGAAGACAAUGUUUCAAUCUGACCAUCUCUGCCAAUUUUAGCUCCCACGCCACCUAUAGAUAGCCAGUUAACUUUCUUUUUGCCCCCAGGCAAUGAGGCCUAGAAGAGGUCAAGGUUAGAAAGGUUAAGCAUUUGAUCACUACAGGUACUUGUAGUACCUAGAGAAGGAACCCAUCCUGGGGUUGGUGGAGUUGGUAUUGCUACUCGUUUUGAUAGUUCUCAUUUACAGAGAAAGAAAAAUAAGCCAAAGCCAGAAAGCAAUCCAAGCCUUACAGUUGUCCAAUACCUCAGGGCCAGUUGGCUAGAAUUUUCUUUUCCCUCAGCCCAUAAUCACUUAGAGUUAGCCAUACAACAAACAGCCUGACAAUCUGACCAGCAUUUCCAUUGAUAUAAAAUGUAAGCAUUCCUUCAUUCUGUAGUUAGGAACUCCAACUUCAGCCUUAUCUCCAACAUAAUUUCCCAAUUUAACCUAUGUACUGAUAUGGACAUUUCUUUGUGAAUAUGCCAGAUUCAAGAAUGUAUUUUUCUAAGGUCAAUAGAGAUACGACAUUUUAAGUCAGGAAAAAUCACCUAUAAAUUAGUAGGAAUAACUGUAGAAGCAUCACAAAAGAUACCCCAUGAAUAGAUGGCAUGGUGUGCAUGCUGACAGCCACGGGGUCAUACUCUGGAGUUUCAACAUAGAGGCUGUGUUUCAAUAAAUAAGACAAAUUGGGGAAUUAAGUAAAACAAAUGGAUGUAACUGAGGCCCCCCCCCAAAAAAAGCCCUCUAUUACUAACCUCAAGAAAAUAUUUAGUUUGACUAAUUUGUGCAGUUUCCAGCUCUUCUACUUGUUCUUGCCUGUAAGAGAAUCACUAAUACUCAAAAGCUGGAUUAUUGAAGAGAAAUUUUAUCUUUAAAUAGAAUCCAUCCACAAUUAUGGUAUAUGUAAAAAAAAUGUAUGACUAUGAAAUAAGUCGCAGCUCUUUGCAGAUAUUGCAAAAUCCUUGCUAGGCAUCUACAUCAUAUUAGUUUUUUAAAAAAUACCUCUGUAACAAGACCUAAAAGUAACCUAACUAUUAAGCAGUGCUUUUUUCUCUGAAAACACACAACCUAAAGAUUUAUCUGUCAUAAAACUGCAUGGUUCCAGAGCUUUAUUUCUGUGUAGAGAUGCUAUUUGUUAGUGAUGGAAACAAAUUACUUUGUUGCUAUGUCUUUUGUGUCUAGCAGUUGAGAGAAUGAUAUGACCAUCAUAUCACUGGAUUAUGGGAAUGAAUGCCCUUUUCAAAAUAAACUUAUUUAUUAAUAUUUUAAUAUUAUUUUAAUAUUAUAAUAUUAAUAAUAUUUUAAUAUUAUUGUUGCUGCUUUAACAGAAAAUGAGCCAUUUGUCCCCAUGCUCCCAAAUUACAAUGAUUUAAAUUAAAAAACUUUUGAAGGAUUUUCCUAAAUAUAUUCUUUUUUAAAGGACUAACUUUGUGCAUUCAUAUAACAACAAUUUGGAAUAAUGUGAAAAAUGGAGGCACAUAAUUUGGGUGGAAAAUGGCGAUUAAAAAUAUAUAUAAGAAAAUUAUUAGCCAUGUGUAACAUAUUUAAAUAAUGACCAGAAUAUUUCAUGAGUACCAACUCUUCCCAUAGUAAUUUUCCUCCAAAAUGCAAUAGCUCAUUCCCUCAACUGCAGACGCUUUGAUUUUUUUUCAAGUUAUAGUGCUGUAGUGCUUGUUUAUGUUUAAAAGUGCACAUUAUGCAGCUCAUUUUAGUAUGCUACUUCUAUGUUUAUUUUUUGUUCUUCUAAUAAAAUGCAUAAACUUCUUGGUUAUGUCUUUUUUUAUGAAUCCAUAUUCACACAUUAGGAGUUCACUUGAAGGCUAUUCAUGCUCUAGUAUAUUAAUCCUAAUAUUUAGUAAUUCUAAAAUGAAAUUUAAAUUUCUGAUUUGGCUCAAUGUUAUAUUUCAUACAUAGAGUAAAUUUAUUUCCAAAUAUACCAUCAGUAUUUUGAAUUAUGUAGAUAAUAUAUCCGUUGUGUUAGACCUAUUACUCUUAUAAGAUUGAAGUUACUGACACAAGAAAAACACUUCUAUUUUAAUAAAAGAAUACUUAAAAUUUUGAGAGAAUGCUUACUAGUUUCUCUUGUGCCUCAGAAAUCCUGAGGCAUAUUCUAAGAUGCAUUAUUAGAAGUUUCUCUUUCCCAGUUAUUCAUGUCUAUCCUGCAUCCCUAGUGUAACAUAUGAAACCAGUGUUGUUUAUUUCAUACUUUCCAGAUGGGCAUCAAUCAUUUCAUAACAAUGAGAUGCAUGAAUUUUUCCAUUAAAAUGUUUUCUCUCACUUAAAAUUGGUUAUCUUCAACAAAUGGCACAGUAAUAAAAGGAUGAUCAUUUUUGUUCUUUAAGAAAGUAAAUGUAAUUUAGUAAUACUUUAUUCUGCCUUAUUUCAAAAUGCUUCAAAAAUGCGAAUCUGGAACUUCUCUGCAUUGACCACUGUUCUGGAGUUGGGCUGAUAGAAAACUGCGGUGAAGAGAGUUUAGAUCAGAGGCUAUGGCAGAGCAAAGUAUUACUGAUGUGUCUCUUAACAGUGAAGAGGGUCGGGGAGGAGGUUGGGUCCUUGUCAAGUGUCAGCUGCCCUAUACAUAGUUCUCUUGCCCCUUGUGCCCUGUUUUACUAUUUCUAAGGUGGUUCCCAUGAUGGCAUUUCUUGAUAAGCCCACUUUGAGCCGUUUAAUGUUUUGUAGGUGUUUCUGUGAGUCUGAUAAUACCAGCACUAAAAACAGUUCAGUAUAUAGACAUUUACAAGAGGUCUUAGGCCUCUUCAGAAUUCAGUUAAUGUCUUUCUCUUUGAGGCUGCUGAAUGUUAGGUAAGAAUUCAGGGCAAGCAUUCCCGACCAUCAUCAAAUUGGAGACUUGGAGUUUCUAUUGGCUGGAAGAAAGUUGACCCACAGGCAAAACCAGAUGUAAACCAAGUUUGUCUUGGGUACUUUUCAAAUUCUUUUCACAGCAUCCUUUUCUCAUCCCUCAUGGUGGCCUCUGGCCCUGGAAAAUCCUCAUGAUAGCAACUUAUCAGGCCUGUUUCCUCUGAUAGAUCUGGACUUUUCCCCUUAAGUGCUUUCCUGUUGGGCUUCUCAGACUAUGGAGAACUGCUCAUAGUUGAGAUCUAAGAGACAAAUUACCCUAUGGUGUUCAAGAAUGGCCGUAUUUAGUAUACUGCCUGUCCUGGAAGUGUUCACAUUUAAAAAGGCAUGACUUUCCAAUGGGCAAAUAUCAGACACCUACAUGCAUAGAUAAGGGAAAUAUGUUUUACUUAAGCAAACUUCUAGGCAUUGAAUCUCAGUGUUUAGGUGCAGAGAUGGAAUUCCUAUAAGCAAUGCAGUCAUUCACCACAUCAGGAAGGCCAAAAAAUGAACACUCUCGUAAUUUUGUUAUUAUCUGGAAAGUUCUGAUAUGAUAAUGAACCUAAAAUACUGAAUAGAUAGUGAACAUCCUAAAAUUCCACUGACCAGAAUCCAUUCCCAUGGUCAUCAUCUGUAGAGGGCAUGAUACAAUGACAGGCCUGAGGUAUGAUUAUAAUUCUGGAGUAAUUUAAAGCCUAUAUUUGUUAAACUUUAACAGAUGGACACACAUUCUCUGAUUUUCUACUUGGCUCUUUCCUGUACUAGAAAUGCGCAUUUAACUAAACCUUCCCAGCUUUUCUGUUCAGUGCCUGACUUACACUACUCCCUUAGGCAGGAGGACAGUGGGUGUCUGGGGAAUAAAAGCCAAGAGCUCCAAACAGAGGAUUUUGGAUACAAAGGGCAGCCACCAGGAAAUAGCUUUGUGAGAGGGACAGACUAUCUGAUUCCCAUUUGUACAAACAUGUCCAAAGCAAAAGCACAGCAUUCUAAAGUGGAUGCAGAAAUUAGUAUACAAUGGCAGUUCUGGCCAGUGCAGCCCAGCAUUUUUCUGUUGUGCAUGGAAAGAACACAGUGAAAAGGCAGGCAGGGCAUCCGGUGCAAAGUGCAACAGACAUAGACACACAAAUCCAGUUUUCCUGAUGAGAGAGGGAGCUAUCUCUUCAUAAGUGAUGCAAUGCAAUGCAGGCAUGUACAAGUACAAGGAAAGAUUUAUUUUUAAAAAAUCAUAGUGUAACUGGAUGAAUACCAGCAACAGCACCUGCUAAAGCAAACAGCCUGUUCAUUAAAAACUGGACUUGAGGGAAUGGAGAAAGAAUCUGAGGAGCCUGCAGUCAGCAUGCUUGCAGAGACCUUAUGGCUACAGAAGACGAUGAUUAACCCAUAGAGGUUCAAUGUAGUUUUCAAGAAGAGGGUGGGAAAGCAUAAGAUGGGGACUAAGACUUUGCCUUUAACCUUCAUGACAUGAAGAAUUGAAUGACUCUUUGUUGGAAAAAAUGGCAGUUAUGAGAUAAUUGGAUCCAUGUUAAUUAUAUAUAUUUCUGUAUAUAUAGUAAGUGGUUAUUGAUGUGCCUUUGUUAACCAUUUCACUAUUUAAUAAAUGUGUGUGUAGUUUA